GGUGUGCAUGUGUGGGUGUUGGGGGAUAAUAGGGCUGUUUUAUUUUUCUUCCACAGAAUGUGAAGAAACAAUAGCUAUGCAUAAAUGGGUACUGCUGUGGGUACGGUGUAAGAACAUUUCCUUAGGAAUGAUUAGGACUAUUUGAACUUAACGAUGUGAGGGAGAAAGCACUUGUUUGUGGGUGGCCUUAAACUUUUAGAUGGCAAAAAGCCAAUAGGCAGGGCUAGAUUACAAAGGAGAGUGCUUGAGUCUCUGUGAUUAACCAAGGAGACACUGCUACAUGAAAACAAGAACAAGGCCUCACCUCGAAGGAAAAAUAGUCCAAACUCUCUUUAUAAAAUGAAUGGCUCUGGCUGUCGGCUCAUUUUGUUGUCUCUGUGUGCAUGUAUUUGACAUCACCUAGAAAAGCAUUUGAAAAAAUAUAUAUAUUUUUAAAUGACCCUUUGGUACCUAAAGGCUGAGAAUAGGGUGUCUUGCUCUGGCUGGCACAACUCCUCGAGCUGCGAACAGACCUGGAGAAAGUCCAGUGGUAACUCCGAGAUGAGAAGUGCCUAGAAAGAUGGGUCCAAAAGCAGAAGACAUGACCUUGGAGAGUCUGGCUGGGAGGAAAGGAGACCUCCCCAAACCAUGAGUGGCACAGACCAUGUCAGACCAUGAGUGGCAUAGAAAAGCUCGCCCGUGCUUCGUGGGGGAAUGGAGCCCCUGGAGUGGUUGUGCAGACCAGUGCAAGCCUACAACCCGUGUGCGGAGGCGCUCGGUGCAGCAGGAGCCUCAGAACGGCGGGGCGCCCUGCCCACCCCUGGAAGAGAGAGCUGGCUGCCUGGAGUACUCCACCCCGCAGGGCCAGGACUGCGGGCACACCUAUGACCAGUGAUCCCAGGCCUGCUUUUGUGACACCCCAUUGUGUCAGAGGGCGUUAUGAAAUUCUCAAAGCAAAUUUAAUUUACUUUCAUGUUCAAAUUCCUGCCUUUAUAACUACCUCUGCAUUCAACAAGGAGAGAACACGACAAGCUACGUCUCCACACUGGUCUACACACACAGAGGAUGCUGGAUACUGUAUGGAGUUUAAGACAGAGUCCUUGACUCCUCACUGUGCUCUGGAAAACUGGCCCUUGACUAGAUGGAUGCAGUAUCUCCGAGAGGGAUACACGGUGUGUGUGGAUUGUCAGCCUCCAGCUAUGAACUCUGUGAGCCUUCGUUGUUCUGGAGAUGGCCUGGACUCCGAUGGAAAUCAGACUCUCCAUUGGCAAGCAAUUGGUAAUCCUCGGUGUCAAGGAACUUGGAAAAAAGUUCGGCGAGUAGACCAGUGUUCUUGUCCAGCUGUUCACAGUUUUAUUUUUAUAUAGAUGGUGAUAUAAAUAUUUCCAAAUGCAUUUGUAAACAUUCUAAAUAUUCUCAAGUCAUGUUCAAUGUUUCCUAAACCUUCAAUUUUGGCCAAAGUCCCCAAACACAUCAUUGCCACACUCUGAAGUAGAGAAAGAAAAUUUAGGGGCCAGUUCUCAAGGAACACAGGUCCUUUAUUUUUAUUUUAACUAAGUUGAAGACCCACUCAAAAAGCUCUUGUGGUUUUAUGUUCUUGACCUUUCAACUGGAGUCCUCUCAUUCAGCAGGUGGCCCGUGAGACACAGAAUACAUGUCUGUUUGCUAAAGUAAAAUUACUGUAACUCAGUCCGAUUAUUGGUGACGGAAGUGUCAUUUAAGGGGAUCUAUGUUUUGAACCUUGCAGUCUAUUUUAUAAUCUUUUAAAAGUUUCUCACUUUAAAACAUGUAUACAGGUAUGCACACUCUACACAUAUAUUUCCAUAUAUUUAAUAUUCCAUAAAUUCUGAAAUAAUUUCAAGCAAAUUAUCACAAAUAAUUUUUCCACAGGGCAAAUUAUUUAAAAUUUUAGUAAGCAUUCUGUAAUGAAAAACCAAGUUAUACUAAAAACAUUUUUUGAAGAAGAAAUUUUUUUUUUGCUUAAGAAGUGAAAGGAUCAAAUGCUCAUUGUAGGUCAAUGGGAGUUCUUUUAAAUGUUAUAAUUUUCAUGAAAAGAAAUGUUGACACCAGUGAAUGAAACAAUUGCUUUCAUUCUGAAAAUUCUACCACCAUUUGCAUCUAAGAUUAUUUCCAAGGCUUAAAGCCUGAAGCUGAAUAAAAUAAUCUUUCAGAGUCCAGCUUCAAGUUUAGUUGAUGUAAGCUCACUAUUUUUUUCCUACCGCAUGCAUUUUCUAAUGUUUGGGGUGGAUGGUGUGUCGGUUAUGGAAGGCAUAGACGUCAUUACAGGUGCUACGAUCUCACACACACACAAGGAAAUGUUAGUCUCCUUAUUUUAUGAUUGGAAAAUCAAUGACCUAGAGGCAAAAUGGCAUGUUUAAGGACCUGGGAUGACAAGUCAUUCUGCAGUCAGCCACAGAGCCAAAUUUGGACUCCUCAACCAGAACUCCAUGAAAAGCCUGACUUUGCCAAACACUGUGCUGGAAAAGCUAAGCCCCUUUCAUUUGUGAAGUAAAUUUUAAAUUCAAGAUAUUUAGUUUAGAGAAUUGAGUCUUGAGAUGUAAACUACAUGAGAUUUCUUUGGUUUCAAUUGAAUAAUAUUCACUAACAAAUGAUUUACUAAAAUACGUAUUUCUUGGUCCUUAUCAUGUAAUGACAGAUUCACAACAGCAAUAAGGAUGGAGAUUUCCCCAAUAAUUAAUAACACCGAGAGUAGCAAUAUUUUUUACUGUAUUUUCAUUUAAUUGUCAAAGUUGUUUUUGUGGAAAAUUAAAUUCUUCAGAAAUUAAUAAUAAAAUAUGUGAGUCUCAUCAAGGCUAGCAACUUUAAGUCAGUAUUAACAUUUUCAUACUGUUUCUAACAUUUAUUAAGCUAGAUUUUUGAAGCUAUGUCUGGGUAAUUUCCAAUGUUACUUAAAAGUUUUUUUUUCUUUGAGACAGAGUCUCACUCUGUUGCCCAGGCUGGAGUGCAGUGGCCCCAUCUCGGCUCACUGCAAGCUCCGCCUCCCGGGUUCACGCCAUUCUUCUGCCUCAGCCUCCCAAGUAGCUGGGACUACAGGCGCCGUCAUCACGCCUGGCUAAUUUUUUGUUUUUUUUUUUUAGUAGAGACAGGGUUUCACUGUGUUAGCCAGGGUGGUCUCGAUCUCCUGACCUCGUGAUCCACCCACCUCGGCCUCCCAAGGUGCUGGGAUUAUGGGCGUGAGCCACUGCGCCUGGCCUGUUACUUAAAAUUUUUAUACUAGUAAAUAAACUUUUUGUUCACAUUUAUAAAAGCUCUAUAUUUGUUUGACUAGAAAAUAACCCAAAUUUUCUGGACCAGUCAGAGAAUGAUAAAAUUUCACCAAAAAUAAAACAAAAAAAUCCUUCAGAACUGAUAGGUAUAGGUACAACAACUACUAAUAGCAAUAAAGCAAUGGUGCUUUUAUAGUUCCGAUAUGUGUUAUAACAUUUAACAUAAUUGAGGUGUAUAAAAUAAAUUUUUCACCUUAUGCAUUUAAUUUUUGGUGGAUGACCAGUAAUUGCUUUCUUAUUGAAGUUAAAUUUUUGUUAUUUCUAUUCUUGAGAAAAUUUUAUGGGCUAGAGGAGUUAACUGUUAAAUAACAGUUUUGAAAAGCUUGUUAUUAAUUUUAGCAAAGCCCAAGGGAAAUAGUUCAGAACUGAAACAUGUAGUCCAAGUGAUGAAUGAAAAACCAAAAGUUUUUAUUUUCAAAUUUAAAAAUCAAAGUAUAUAAGACCUCUUGGCACUCUUUUUUAAUAAGUACCUUAGUCUUAGGGCCCUAUCCCCAGGCACUCUAAAAAGAUUUACGAACUCUAAAAUCCCUUAAUAGACUGAUUUUCAAAAGUGCUCAUGGAAAAUAAUUCGAACAAAAAUAAAUACAGCCACCAGGAAAGAAGGGAAAAGAAGCAAGGGAUAAUGGCCAUUUUUGAAGAGAAAAGUGAAAAACAAGUGAAGGAAAAAAAGAAUAGAAAAAGGAAUAAGGUAACUAUAAUCACAGUAUUCUUUUUGGAGUUUUGCUUUGGUUUUUAUUCGAGAAUGUUACAAUUAAGCAUAAACCGCAACAGCAAUAAUUUAAAGUGUUUGGUUAUCAUCUGGCAUAAAAAUUUCAGUUAGCUAUCUUUUCUAGAUGUGCACAAAAUUGAUGUUAAUAAAACUGGUUCCUGCCCUCUAA